CUAGUUGGUGGAGUUCUGCCCGGAUGGAAGCUCCGGCCGCGGAGUGAUGGUGGCCUCAGCGAAGAUGGGCCGGGCAGGGACCAUGGCGGUGGCAGCAGAGGUGGCAGGGGCGGGGCGGCUGGCGGUAGAGGAGGCUGUGGUCCUCAGGGGGCUGUAGGUGGAGGUAUGGCUCGGGCCAGCAGCGGGAACGGCAGCGAGGAGGCCUGGGGGGCACUUCGGGCGCCGCAACAGCAGCUUCGAGAGCUGUGCCCAGGAGUGAACAACCAGCCCUACCUCUGUGAGAGUGGUCACUGCUGCGGGGAGACUGGCUGCUGCACCUACUACUAUGAGCUCUGGUGGUUCUGGCUGCUCUGGACUGUCCUCAUCCUCUUUAGCUGCUGUUGCGCCUUCCGCCACCGACGAGCUAAACUCAGGCUGCAACAACAGCAGCGGCAGCGUGAAAUCAACUUGUUGGCCUAUCAUGGGGCAUGCCAUGGGGCUGGUCCUUUCCCUACCGGUUCACUGCUUGACCUUCGCUUCCUCAGCACCUUCAAGCCCCCAGCCUACGAGGAUGUGGUUCACCGCCCAGGCACACCACCCCCCCCUUAUACUGUGGCCCCAGGCCGCCCCUUGACUGCUUCCAGUGAACAAACCUGCUGUUCCUCCUCAUCCAGCUGCCCUGCCCACUUUGAAGGAACAAAUGUGGAAGGUGUUUCCUCCCACCAGAGUGCCCCCCCUCAUCAGGAGGGUGAGCCCGGGGCAGGGGUGACCCCUGCCUCCACACCCCCCUCCUGCCGCUAUCGCCGUUUAACUGGCGACUCCGGUAUUGAGCUCUGCCCUUGUCCUGCCUCCGGUGAGGGUGAGCCAGUCAAGGAGGUGAGGGUUAGUGCCACCCUGCCAGAUCUGGAGGACUACUCCCCGUGUGCACUACCCCCAGAGUCUGUACCGCAGAUCUUUCCCAUGGGGCUGUCUUCCAGUGAAGGGGACAUCCCAUAAGUAGUUUUGAGAGGGUGGAUGGGUUACUUGCCCACCAGAAACAGCCCUAGUCCCAACUCCUUGCGUUCCUUUGGCCCCUCCCUGCCUACCUAGAAUCUGCCUGAAAGGGCUGGAGAGGGGCAGUAUUGGGGGACUGUGCUAGCUUUACCCCCGCAGGACAUACACAGGAGCCUUUGAUCUCAUUAAAGAGAUGUGAACCA